ACCUGCUCACUCUGUCACCGAGGCUAGAGUACAGUGGCACAAUCACAGCUCAUUGCAGCCUCAACCUCCCAGGCUCAAUCGAUCCUUCCAACUGAGCCUCCCUAGCAGCUGGGACUAUUAGUGCACACCACCACACCUAGGUAAUUUUUGUAUUUUUUGUAGCGAUGGAGUUUCGCCAUGUUGCUUAGGUUGGUUUCAAACUCCUGGGCUCAAGUGAUCCACCCACCGCAGCCUCUCAAAGUGCUGGGAUUAUAGGUGUGAGCCACCCAUGCCCAGCCUUACCUUUUUAUUGAAAGAUGUUGUUUUUAUAGGCUGUAAAAUUCAAAGUUGGUUCCCUAGUCCAUAGAUUAAAAAAAAAAAAAAUCAAAGUUGGGAAUUAUUUUCUUUAGAUAGCAUUCUAUUGACUCCUGGAUUUUGUCAUUUCUUUUGAGAAGUCAGCUGUCAUUUUUAUUGCUUCACUGCUUUUUAAGGUUUUCCUCUUUUUCUUUGUUUUUCAGCAGUUUGACUAUGAUGUCUGUGUGUUCUUUUCUUUGUAUUGGCCAAAUAAUUGGGUUGCUGAGUUUCUUAAAUCUGUGGGUUGAUCUCUUUCAUUUGUUUUGAACAUUUUAGUAUUGCUUCUGCUCUAUGCUGUCUUCUGAGACUCAUUUAUUCACGUCUUUUAUUCCACGUCUUUUAUGUUCUUAUCUGUGUUUACCAUUCAUUUUUCUAAUUGAGUUUGAAUAUUUUUUAUUGACCUAUCUUCCAAAUCAUUAAUCUUGUCUCCUGCUAAGUCCAAUUUACUGUUAAUAUCUUAUAUUAAAUUCUUAAUUAUAGAUACUGUAGUUCUCAGUUCUAAAGUAUCCAUUUGAUUUUUUUUAUAGAUUUCAGCCAAUUCUGUGAUAAAAUUAUUUAUCCUUUCAUUUACUUUGGUCUUUUCCUCUGUUUCUUGACUUUAUUAAUCUUGGUUAUUUCAAAGUUCUUGACUACUAAACUUCAGUAAUUGGGCCAUCCAUAGGUCUGCUUCUAAUGUCUGUUUUUUCUCUUGAUUACUAGCUGUGGGCAUUUACCUCCACACAUGCUUAAAAAACUUAUUAUAUACCAAACAUUAUAUAAAAGAAUCAUAGUGGAUGCAUAUAUCUUCCACCAUCAAGGUUUGCCCCUUUCUUCUGUUAAUUAAAUACUUCAGUCUAGUCUGACGUAUUUCAGGGAUUGAGCUAGGUCACUGCUGGGUUGCAAUCCUGGUAAGCCCCAAACUUACUUUGGUUCAUCCUUAUUAGAGUAUGGUCCUCCAGGGCUUUCAGUUGAAAGCCUAAUAGGCUAUUUGUCUCCUUAGACAUGAAAGCCUUUAGGAGGUUCACUUCUGCCCCUAAGGUUUUCAGCUUAGUUAUUUAGCCUACCACUACUUCACAUCAUUUCAAAAUUGACUAAAUGUCUUGAGGAAGACCCCAACCAAGUAAGUAUUUCGAGUCCAUCAAAUCUCCAGCUUUGUUACCCCAGCUUUGAAGAAUACCAAAAUCUCUACUGGGUUGUCUUCAGCAGCAGCCUUCUUCCAGAAGUUGGGUAUUUGGAGGUCCCUCAAGAUUGCAGUUUUGUCUGUCCAGCCCCAGGUGACCAUCGAAAGCAUUGUGGUUUCUCUUUCCCCAAUGAUAACCACACCCUAAUCCCAAGCCCACGUCCAGGAUCAACACAUGCACCAAAGGCUCGUGCGCACACACCAAAGGCGCGCGCGCACACACACACACACACACACACACACACACAAGCUAUUGAUUGUUGAUUCCCUCUGAACAUUCUCAGUCUGUUAGUCCAUCUAGUCCUUGUUGCUUCCACAAGUAUUGGAUGCUUUAAGAAAUGAUUUUUGUAAUUUAUUUGGCUUUUUCUAGUCAUUGGCAGGAGUAUUAGCCUGCCAAACCAUACUAUAUCCUACUUGGAAGCAGAAUCUGUACAGAUGUUUUUGAGGGCUUGCCAUGUGCCAGAUGCUCUUGUAGCUUCUAGGUAUAGGAUUGCCCUGCCCUCUCAGAGCCUCUAGUCUAAACUAGGUAAAACAGACAUAUACACAAAUAAUACAGCAUGCCAAAUACUGUCAUAGAGGUGUGUACAGGGGUAGGAAAAAGGAGACAAAUGUGAACUAGCACCACCUGUUUAGAAAAUUGCAAGUUUUAUAAAUUUUACAUGAUUGCAGGUUAGAGAUCAAAGUGGUAGAAUAAUGAAAAAUGAGGUUGGCAAGACAGGCAGAAGCCUGAUGGUGAAAGGCCCCGUAUGCCAUGGUAAUGCUUAGGUAUAGCUUCUACCUAGAAGUAUCUGCCCUUCAUGCAGGAUGGAGAGCAGUUUAAGAAUUAAGCCUAGAGAAUUGCGAUCAGAUUUUUCUUUUAGAAAGAUUACUUAAGUGUCAUUGUGAAAUGUGAAUUCGAGGAGGGCAAGAAACAAGCCAAAGGGCCAGAGAGGAAACUGUGAGAGUUGACCCAAUAUGAAACACAUUGGUUAUCAUCAUCAGCAGAUUUGAAAGGUGUCAAAGGGGUGGAAUUGAUGAAAUGUAGGGAAUGUUGGGAUUAAGAGAGGGUGAAAGAAAACAGAGAUUCUAGGGUUUCUAGCUUGACUAUAAAUCACCAAGGGAAUAUGGCAGAAAGCGAUGAGGUCAAUGUUAGACAUACUGUGUAUUCCCAUUUCAUUAGCUCUAUUACGGUUUUUGUUAUAUAAUCUGAGAAUGUAGUUUAGGAACCACCACCCUGUCAGGGGGCGGACCCCAAGUUAUCUUCUUGAAACUCCUACAGUGAAAUAAGAGAGAGAGCCCUAGGCCAUUGCCUUCACCCUGGAUUUUACAAGACACCCUCUGAUUUUGUCCAUUUUGUAUACCAGGCUUCCACUUAAACAUUGUAUUUGAAGAAAAUUCUCCAUACUAAAAGAAAAAAAAUUCCUCAGCAGUGUAAGUGUCUUCUUCUGGUGGGAUAUGUGGGUAAUACCCUCUCUUGCAUGUUGUUCUUCCAUCUUGACAGAAGAACAUCUUCAGUGGCAUUUGGGGGCCACAAUCCUUUAUUUGCAGUAAGUAGGUGCUAUUCCACUGUCUUCUAGCAUCCAUUGUUGCCAAUGAGGAGUUCAAAGCCAGUUUCUUUUUCUUUUAUUUGUUAUUUGUCAUUUCCUCCUCAAAGCAUAUGUGAUUUUUCUCUUCAUAUUUAGAGUGAAGGAAUUUUACCAGAAUGUGGUCAGGUGUGUAUCCUUCAAGGCUUUUCGGUCUCCAGAUAAAUCUUUUUGCAGCUAAGGGAAAUGUUUCUCCUUUCAAAUUCCCCCUUACAUGCUGGUUCUUCCAGAUCUGUCCUCCAAGUCUCACAGUUUGCGUCUCUGCAUCCCUGCUUUGGGUAAGACAGGUCCACUUGAUCUACUAGGCCACUAAUUGGGUUUUGGCAAUUAACUGUCUUUUUAAAAAUUUCAUCAGUGGAGCUUUUUUGUGUGUGGAAAAUUAUGCUUUUAAUUCUAAGAGACAUCUUUGGUGUCAUAAUUGAACUUGGUCUUUUUAUUAUUAUUAUUAUUAAAAUUCUUAUCUGCCUCUUUUUCUGGUUCUGUUAAUCUAAGAUUCACCACCUCAAGGAGUGCUCAAAUGCUUUUUCUACCCAUGACUGCUGGAUCCCAUUAAGCAAUUCUCUUUCUUUCCUACUUCUUGAUCCAACUACCAGUAUCUCAGGCAGGGAGGUGGCAAAGCAGCCUCUGGUUCAUCAGUGUAUGAGCCAGUGCACAUGGGAUGUCAUUAGACCCCAGCCAAGCUUUGUGGCUGCCACGCGUGGCAUUUUUCUAGCCUGAGAUAGGGAAGAGUCAAGCUUCUUCCCUUCUCUGGCUUCUUGGGGCCACAGAGAGCAUGAGAUACACCCCAACGAAGCCUCACAGUGACGAACAGUGCCCUUCCUCAUAGGGUUCCAGGGAGGUCAGUAGACCAGACUCUCCAGCGUAUCAGAGUCUCUCCAUGGGGAAAUUUGGCACCAGCUCUCUUUCUGGACUGAGCAGGCCUUGCUCACGCCCGCUGGCACGACUUGCCUGCCAAUCUAUAGCCACCGAGUUCGGGAGUGUUCAUGGAAUUGGGGGUAGACAGAAGCAGCACAAGCACUUUCUUAUCAUCUCUUCAAAAGCCCCCAGCAAGUAGAGAAAAAAGAAAGACCACAAGACCACCAGACUAGAUGAUCUCUAAGCCUCCAUCCAAUGCCGACAUUUUACAGUUAUACACAUUUAUGGUCUCCAACUCAGCUCAGUCCUCAGUACCCUUGGGCCACACUUUUGUAAGUCUUCCCAGCAUGCUCUGCUUCCCCAAAGGGAGUAUUUGAGACUUUUAUUUCUCUCCUCAAGCCCUCUGUUUAUCCUUCUCCUUGUUCACUGUCAGCCCAUGACUUUGAAUUUCUCUUCACAAAAAAAAAGACAGACUCUUGGAUAUUGAGUUGUUCUUUGCUUUCCUGUAAUCCUUUCUCCUUUGCCUGCUCGCCUGCUUGCCUGCCUGCUGUCCAUCUUUCCAUCCUGCUGGACUCUGUCUUCUCCUGUGUGUUCUGUGAUAGUGUGUGCUCCCAGUUUUCCCAUCUCUCUGGGUACCCCCUUUCGCUUUAUGUUGCUGUCAGUCUCACCCAGUUCUGAUCCUUCUCCCAUAUUACAGGCUCCUGGGGGAUCUUUUCAGUGCAUAAAGUUGACCAUAUCACCCCUUGCUUUAAACCUCUUAAUGACAGGAACAGGCAAAACAUGUCUGUAGUGAUAGAAGUCAUAAGAGUGGUUACCUCCAGGCAGGUGAAAUAGGAAUCAAUUGCAAAAGGACAUGAGGGAGCCUUCUAGGUUGUUGGAAUUAUUUUGUAUCUUACUUCGGGAAGUGGUUACAUUGUUCUAUACAAACACAAAAAUUCACUGAGCUGUACAUUAAGAUAGUGCAUUUUACUAUAUGUAUACCUCAGUUUUAAAAAGAUGAAACCUGAAGGUUUAAAUCCAAACUCCUGAAGGUUAAAAUCCGAACUCCUGAAAAUAGUCCACAGAUUCCUAUUCCUUCCUCCCUCAAGUCUUGCCUCGAGCAUAAUUUUCUUGUGAGACCCAUCCUGGCUUCCUCAGGAUAUGACUUCCACACUCAGGACUGUAAGCUUAGGCCUGUCCUAAUCCUGAAGAGACUUUAUUGUAACUGUACAUGUACUUCCCUCACUAGACAGGGGGCUCAGUUUCAUUGCACCCCUAGUGCCUUGUGCAGUGGCUGGCACAUAGACCCCAGCCUGCAGGAUGUUUCCUCAAUGAGGGGAAGGCUGCUGCACAAUGGCAGUUUUUGAUACUCCUGAGGAGGCCUUUGGUGUCUUACGUCCAGUCUGUGUUCAGCUCACAAAGACCCAGACAGUGGAGAAUGUGGAGCAUCUGCAGACACGACUACAAGCUGUGAGUGACAGUGCCCUUCAGGAACUUCAGCAGUACAUCCUCUUCCCUCUGCGAUUUACCCUGAAGACCCCAGGUCCCAAAAGAGAGCGUUUGAUCCAAAGUGUGGUGGAAUGCCUCACAUUUGUCCUUUCUUCAACAUGUGUGAAAGAACAGGAGCUUCUCCAGGAACUCUUUUCAGAACUCUCUGCUUGUCUGUAUUCACCCAGCUCCCAAAAACCUGCGGCUGUGUCCGAGGAGUUGAAAUUGGCUGUGAUCCAGGGACUUAGCACAUUAAUGCACUCAGCUUAUGGGGACAUCAUUCUGACUUUUUAUGAGCCCUCCAUUCUGCCACGUUUAGGAUUUGCUGUAUCUUUACUGUUAGGCCUUGCAGAACAGGAGAAAUCAAAGCAAAUUAAAAUUGCUGCCUUAAAAUGUUUACAGGUUCUACUCUUGCAGUGUGAUUGUCAGGACCAUCCAAGGUCAUUGGAUGAACUUGAACAAAAGCAGCUGGGGGAUUUGUUUGCCUCUUUUUUACCUGGAAUCUCAACUGCACUGACCAGGCUUAUCACAGGAGACUUUAAACAAGGUCACAGCAUUGUCGUAUCUUCCCUAAAGAUCUUUUACAAGACAGUGAGCUUCAUUAUGGCUGAUGAACAGCUCAAAAGAAUCUCAAAGGUCCAAGCAAAACCUGCAGUUGAGCACAGAGUAGCAGAGCUGAUGGUUUACAGGGAAGCAGAUUGGGUAAAAAAGACUGGCGACAAGUUGACUAUCCUUAUUAAAAAGAUAAUUGAGUGUGUUUCUGUUCACCCACACUGGAAGGUGAGACUGGAACUGGUAGAACUUGUGGAGGACCUUCUUUUGAAGUGCAGUCAAUCAUUGGUCGAAUGUGCUGGUCCCCUUCUGAAGGCCUUAGUGGGACUAGUAAAUGAUGAGAGUCCUGAAAUCCAAGCCCAGUGCAAUAAAGUUCUGAGACAUUUUGCAGAUCAAAAAGUAGUGGUGGGCAACAAAGCCCUCGCUGACAUCUUGUCAGAAAGCCUGCAUUCCCUUGCCACAUCUCUUCCUCGCCUAAUGAACUCCCAAGAUGACCAGGGCAAAUUCUCUACUCUUUCCUUGUUACUUGGUUAUCUGAAACUCUUGGGCCCAAAAAUAAACUUUGUCCUCAACUCUGUGGCCCAUCUCCAGCGGCUUUCCAAAGCACUCAUCCAAGUUCUAGAGCUAGACGUGGCUGACAUCAAGAUUGUUGAGGAACGGCGUUGGAACUCUGAUGAUCUGAAUGCUUCUCCAAAGACCUCAGCCACACAGCCUUGGAACCGCAUCCAGAGGAGAUAUUUCCGCUUCUUCACUGAUGAGAGAAUCUUCAUGCUCUUGAGGCAGGUUUGUCAGCUACUUGGUUAUUAUGGGAAUCUUUAUUUGCUUGUGGAUCACUUUAUGGAACUUUACCAUCAAUCUGUGGUUUACCGGAAGCAAGCUGCCAUGAUCCUUAAUGAACUGGUUACAGGGGCUGCUGGGCUGGAGGUUGAGGAUCUUCACGAAAAACAUAUUAAAACAAACCCAGAAGAACUGAGAGAGAUUGUGACAUCUAUACUUGAAGAAUACACAAGUCAAGAAAAUUGGUAUUUGGUUACCUGUCUUGAAACUGAGGAAAUGGGAGAGGAGCUGAUGAUGGAGCACCCAGGCCUCCAAGCCAUCACGUCUGGUGAACACACCUGCCAAGUUACAUCUUUUCUAGCCUUCUCAAAGCCAAGUCCCACUAUUUGCUCCAUGAACAGUAACAUCUGGCAAAUAUGCAUUCAGUUGGAAGGAAUUGGCCAGUUUGCAUAUGCACUAGGAAAAGACUUCUGUUUGCUCUUGAUGUCAGCCCUUUAUCCAGUACUGGAGAAGGCUGGAGACCAAACCCUACUCAUUAGUCAGGUGGCUACCAGCACCAUGAUGGACGUUUGCCGUGCUUGUGGCUACGACUCCCUGCAGCACCUGAUCAAUCAAAAUUCAGACUAUUUAGUGAAUGGGAUCUCUUUAAAUCUGCGUCAUCUGGCUCUGCAUCCUCAUACCCCAAAGGUCCUGGAAGUCAUGCUGCGGAACUCAGAUGCUAACCUGCUUCCUUUGGUGGCAGAUGUGGUUCAAGAUGUCUUGGCCACCCUGGACCAAUUUUACGAUAAGAGAGCUGCUUCCUUUGUCAGCGUUCUGCAUGCUCUGAUGGCAGCAUUAGCCCAGUGGUUCCCAGACACAGGUAAUCUUGGGCACCUCCAAGAGCAAAGUUUAGGAGAAGAGGGAAGUCAUUUGAACCAAAGACCAGCAGCUCUUGAGAAGAGCACCACCACAGCUGAAGACAUCGAACAGUUUUUGCUGAACUACCUCAAAGAGAAGGAUGUGGCAGAUGGAAAUGUCUCGGAUUUUGAUAAUGAAGAAGAGGAACAGUCAGUCCCUCCCAAAGUGGAUGAGAAUGACACCCGUCCAGAUGUGGAGCCACCACUGCCAUUGCAGAUCCAAAUAGCCAUGGACGUGAUGGAACGCUGCAUCCACUUGUUGUCAGAUAAAAAUCUGCAAAUCCGCCUGAAGGUCUUGGAUGUGCUGGAUCUGUGUGUGGUUGUUCUUCAGUCCCACAAAAACCAGCUGCUUCCCUUGGCUCAUCAGGCCUGGCCCUCGCUCGUUCACCGACUCACACGGGACGCCCCCCUGGCAGUGCUUAGAGCCUUCAAGGUUUUACGUACCCUGGGAAGCAAGUGUGGUGACUUUCUUCGCAGCCGGUUCUGCAAAGAUGUCCUGCCAAAGCUGGCUGGCUCCCUAGUCACCCAGGCCCCCAUCAGUGCCAGGGCUGGACCAGUUUACUCGCACACGCUGGCCUUCAAGUUGCAGCUGGCUGUCUUACAGGGCCUGGGCCCCCUCUGUGAGAGACUGGACCUAGGUGAGGGUGACCUGAAUAAAGUGGCUGAUGCCUGCUUGAUUUACCUCAGUGUCAAACAGCCCGUGAAAUUACAAGAGGCUGCCAGGAGCGUCUUCCUCCACUUGAUGAAGGUGGACCCAGACUCCACCUGGUUCCUCCUGAACGAGCUUUACUGCCCCGUGCAGUUCACACCUCCCCACCCCAGCCUCCACCCUGUGCAGCUGCACGGGGCCAGCGGGCAGCAGAACCCCUACACGACCAACGUGCUCCAGCUGCUCAAGGAGCUGCAGUGACCCUGCUCCCCCACCACAGAGGCCACCGAUCCCUCCCCUACUGCCAGCCAGAAGCUGGGCUGACCCCACCCCGGCCAUAGGCGGUGGCAGCGGCAGCAGAGAAGGUGAAUUAGUUAGCCAAUCGAUUUAUAAAUUGAUCGAUCACACAACUGCUUAGAAAUGGAUUGAAGGAAAGUAGCUGACUAUUAUUUAUGUUUCAUACCUUGUGUUGUCAAGUGACAUUGUCUGGUGGCUCUAAGGGUUUAACCCCUUAGCCUACCAUCUCUAUAGCCCCAGCUCCCUCACAGGCCACACACACACACACACAAGAGGUCAGUUCCCCUCCAUCUGCAUACACCUCCCUGUCUUCAAAUAAUGAGAUGGAACUAAUUUGUUUUACCUAACCUGAUCUUUGGGAAACAAACGGAAAUAAAGACACUUCUUGGAUGAAAAGUA